AGAACAGGAAGCGGAGGCAUAAGCAGAGAGGAUUCUGGAAAGGUCUCUUUGUUUUCUUAUCCACAGAGAAAGAAAGAAAAAAAAUUGUAACUAAUUUGUAAACCUCUGUGGUCAAAAAAAAAAAAAAAAAAAAAAGCUGAACAGCUGCAGAGGAAGACACGUUAUACCCUAACCAUCUUGGAUGCUGGGCUUUGUUAUGCUGUAAUUCAUAAGGCUCUGUUUUAUCAGAGAUUAUGGAGCAAGAAAACUGAAGCCAAGCCACAUCAAGGUUUGACAGGGAUGAGAUACCUGUCAAGGAUUCAUAGUAGAGUGGCUUACUGGGAAAGGAGCAAAGAAUCUCUUCUAGGGAUAUUGUAAGAAUAAAUGAGAUAAUUCACAGAAGGGACCUGGAGCUUUUCCGGAAAAAGGUGCUGUGACUAUCUAAGGUAAUUCGUAUGCAAGAAGCUACACGUAAUUAAAUGUGCAGGAUGAAAAGAUGGCACAGGCACUGUUGGUACCCCCAGGACCUGAAAGCUUCCGCCUUUUUACUAGAGAAUCUCUUGCUGCUAUCGAAAAACGUGCUGCAGAAGAGAAAGCCAAGAAGCCCAAAAAGGAACAAGAUAAUGAUGAUGAGAACAAACCAAAGCCAAAUAGUGACUUGGAAGCUGGAAAGAACCUUCCAUUUAUUUAUGGAGACAUUCCUCCAGAGAUGGUGUCAGAGCCCCUGGAGGACCUGGAUCCCUACUAUAUCAAUAAGAAAACUUUUAUAGUAAUGAAUAAAGGAAAGGCAAUUUUCCGAUUCAGUGCCACCUCUGCCUUGUAUAUUUUAACUCCACUAAACCCUGUUAGGAAAAUUGCUAUCAAGAUUUUGGUACAUUCUUUAUUCAGCAUGCUUAUCAUGUGCACUAUUUUGACCAACUGUGUAUUUAUGACCUUGAGCAACCCUCCUGACUGGACAAAGAAUGUAGAGUACACAUUCACUGGAAUCUAUACCUUUGAGUCACUUAUAAAAAUCUUGGCAAGAGGGUUUUGCUUAGAAGAUUUUACGUUUCUUCGUGAUCCAUGGAACUGGCUGGAUUUCAGUGUCAUUGUGAUGGCAUAUGUGACAGAGUUUGUGGACCUGGGCAAUGUCUCAGCGUUGAGAACAUUCAGAGUUCUCCGAGCACUGAAAACAAUUUCAGUCAUUCCAGGUUUAAAGACCAUUGUGGGGGCCCUGAUCCAGUCGGUAAAGAAGCUUUCUGAUGUGAUGAUCCUGACUGUGUUCUGUCUGAGCGUGUUUGCUCUCAUUGGGCUGCAGCUGUUCAUGGGCAAUCUGAGGAAUAAAUGUUUGCAGUGGCCCCCAAGCGAUUCUGCUUUUGAAACCAACACCACUUCCUACUUUAAUGGCACAAUGGAUUCAAAUGGGACAUUUGUUAAUGUAACAAUGAGCACAUUUAACUGGAAGGAUUACAUUGGAGAUGACAGUCACUUUUAUGUUUUGGAUGGGCAAAAAGACCCUUUACUCUGUGGAAAUGGCUCAGAUGCAGGCCAGUGUCCAGAAGGAUACAUCUGUGUGAAGGCUGGUCGAAACCCCAACUAUGGCUACACAAGCUUUGACACCUUUAGCUGGGCUUUCCUGUCUCUAUUUCGACUCAUGACUCAAGACUACUGGGAAAAUCUUUACCAGUUGACAUUACGUGCUGCUGGGAAAACAUACAUGAUAUUUUUUGUCCUGGUCAUUUUCUUGGGCUCAUUUUAUUUGGUGAAUUUGAUCCUGGCUGUGGUGGCCAUGGCCUAUGAGGAGCAGAAUCAGGCCACCUUGGAAGAAGCAGAACAAAAAGAGGCCGAAUUUCAGCAGAUGCUCGAACAGCUUAAAAAGCAACAGGAAGAAGCUCAGGCAGUUGCGGCAGCAUCAGCUGCUUCAAGAGAUUUCAGUGGAAUAGGUGGGUUAGGAGAGCUGUUGGAAAGUUCUUCAGAAGCAUCAAAGUUGAGUUCCAAAAGUGCUAAAGAAUGGAGGAACCGAAGGAAGAAAAGAAGACAGAGAGAGCACCUUGAAGGAAACAACAAAGGAGAGAGAGACAGCUUUCCCAAAUCCGAAUCUGAAGACAGCGUCAAAAGAAGCAGCUUCCUUUUCUCCAUGGAUGGAAACAGACUGACCAGUGACAAAAAAUUCUGCUCCCCUCAUCAGUCUCUCUUGAGUAUCCGUGGCUCCCUGUUUUCCCCAAGACGCAAUAGCAAAACAAGCAUUUUCAGUUUCAGAGGUCGGGCAAAGGAUGUUGGAUCUGAAAAUGACUUUGCUGAUGAUGAACACAGCACAUUUGAAGACAGCGAAAGCAGGAGAGACUCACUGUUUGUGCCGCACAGACAUGGAGAGCGACGCAACAGUAACGUUAGUCAGGCCAGUAUGUCAUCCAGGAUGGUGCCAGGGCUUCCAGCAAAUGGGAAGAUGCACAGCACUGUGGAUUGCAAUGGUGUGGUUUCCUUGGUGGGUGGACCUUCAGCUCUAACGUCACCUACUGGACAACUUCCCCCAGAGGGCACCACCACAGAAACGGAAGUCAGAAAGAGAAGGUUAAGCUCUUACCAGAUUUCAAUGGAGAUGCUGGAGGAUUCCUCUGGAAGGCAAAGAGCCGUGAGCAUAGCCAGCAUUCUGACCAACACAAUGGAAGAACUUGAAGAAUCUAGACAGAAAUGUCCGCCAUGCUGGUAUAGAUUUGCCAAUGUGUUCUUGAUCUGGGACUGCUGUGAUGCAUGGUUAAAAGUAAAACAUCUUGUGAAUUUAAUUGUUAUGGAUCCAUUUGUUGAUCUUGCCAUCACUAUUUGCAUUGUCUUAAAUACCCUCUUUAUGGCCAUGGAGCACUACCCCAUGACUGAGCAAUUCAGUAGUGUGUUGACUGUAGGAAACCUGGUCUUUACUGGGAUUUUCACAGCAGAAAUGGUUCUCAAGAUCAUUGCCAUGGAUCCUUAUUACUAUUUCCAAGAAGGCUGGAAUAUCUUUGAUGGAAUUAUUGUCAGCCUCAGUUUAAUGGAGCUUGGUCUGUCAAAUGUGGAGGGAUUGUCUGUACUGCGAUCAUUCAGACUGCUUAGAGUUUUCAAGUUGGCAAAAUCCUGGCCCACACUAAAUAUGCUAAUUAAGAUCAUUGGCAAUUCUGUGGGGGCUCUAGGAAACCUCACCUUGGUGUUGGCCAUCAUCGUCUUCAUUUUUGCUGUGGUCGGCAUGCAGCUCUUUGGUAAGAGCUACAAAGAAUGUGUCUGCAAGAUCAAUGAUGACUGUACGCUCCCACGGUGGCACAUGAACGACUUCUUCCACUCCUUCCUGAUUGUGUUCCGCGUGCUGUGUGGAGAGUGGAUAGAGACCAUGUGGGACUGUAUGGAGGUCGCUGGCCAAACCAUGUGCCUUAUUGUUUUCAUGUUGGUCAUGGUCAUUGGAAACCUUGUGGUUCUGAACCUCUUUCUGGCCUUAUUGUUGAGUUCAUUUAGCUCAGACAACCUUGCUGCUACUGAUGAUGACAAUGAAAUGAAUAAUCUGCAGAUUGCAGUAGGAAGAAUGCAAAAGGGAAUUGAUUAUGUGAAAAAUAAGAUGCGGGAGUGUUUCCAAAAAGCCUUUUUUAGAAAGCCAAAAGUUAUAGAAAUCCAUGAAGGCAAUAAGAUAGACAGCUGCAUGUCCAAUAAUACUGGAAUUGAAAUAAGCAAAGAGCUUAAUUAUCUUAGAGAUGGGAAUGGAACCACCAGUGGUGUAGGUACUGGAAGCAGUGUUGAAAAAUACGUAAUCGAUGAAAAUGAUUAUAUGUCAUUCAUAAACAACCCCAGCCUCACCGUCACAGUGCCAAUUGCUGUUGGAGAGUCUGACUUUGAAAACUUAAAUACUGAAGAGUUCAGCAGUGAGUCAGAACUAGAAGAAAGCAAAGAGGAGUAAAAUCAAGCUGGAGCCAUCAAGAAUGCAGCUCUGGUGUUUUUUAACCAGCCAGAGGCUCGUGCCACCACUUUUACCCAGGUUAUCCAAGCAAGUUGUACAUGUACAAUCACGUUCUAAAUGAAUUUUGACUGGCCUGCAUGCUACUCAGCUAUGUUCCUUCCCCUGCCAUGGCAAGGAAGUGCUAGACUUGCCCAGCUGCUCUCUGCUGAAUCGUGUGACACAUCACAGCAUGGUCAGGCGAGAUGGGCAAUCCCAACAUCAUAUUUAAUUCUGCUAAUGAGUUUUCUAAUUUAGUCUUUAGCCUUUUAAAACCAAUUGCAUGCUCUAUAGGAUUUGUAAUAUCUAUUUUAAAACAUGAUAGGAAUGUUUAUGGUUCAAUAUAGUCAGGGAUGUAGGAGGGCAUGCAUUUUUUUGUUUCUCUGCUUUUAUUUCAUUAAAAUAAGACCACAACUUUUUAUUGUUGAUUCAGCCUUUAUAAGUAAAUUGUAUUACCAAAAUAAGCCUCACAGGGUUUUUUUCUGAUAGUACUGCCACUUUCAGAUCAUUAUAUUCAGAUCUAUGAAUAUAAUUUUCAGCCUAUCCAAUUCAUGUGCUCCAGAUGAAAAUGUUUGCUUUCAUGUUUUGGGGGAAAGGUUCUGUAAAAAAAAAAAAAAAGAAAAAAAAGAAAGAAAGAAAAAAGAAAAAAAAAAGAAUAGGGUGAUCCUGAGGUUUGGAGAUGAAGGGCCAUAGUCUGUAUGCAUUUGGGCAACACAUAUCUUGGAUUUUCAUGUAGGUUGGGAAAAGUUAUGUCUGCAAAACCAUAGUGAUCAUUGUAACUUAAAAAAGGAAACAUCAUGAUAUAUGGGAUGAAAAUUCAUUAUAUCUUGAUCAUUAAGUAAUUGGCCUAGUGUACCCAUUUGUUAUUUGAAAUGUCAAUGAUUUAUGUUAAUUUCUCCCUAAAUGUUCUAUCCAAAACUGACCAGGCAAAAAAGAGACUUGGAAAAUUUACUAUUUUCAGUUAUUAAUUAUUAAUUUUAGUUUUGUGAGGAGUAAAGGGAAUCUCCCAAGAUUAUUGUAGAUUUGUGGCGUAAUGAGCUUUUAUUUUAUUCUGUUCACUCAACUUUCUCCAUUGCUUACUGGAAUCUCAGCCAGAGUGCGGGUUCUGGGAGGGAAAUUUUGAAGGAAAUGUAAAGAGUUCAUAAAUAUUGGGCAGUUUUCAAGGCUUCUGGUGACAAGGAAUAUCUAAUUAGUUUGGGGUUGUCUCUAGGUUUAAUUUAUGCAUAGUCUUAUUUUCCUUAGGGAUAACUGAGAAUUAGUUGCAGAAUGCAAAAAAAAUGAGAAAUAAAAUUAUCAAUGGAAAAUAGUAACAAAGAUACAGUCCAUGGUGAUUUAUGCAAUUUUUAUUCAGCACCAAAUUUUUAGAUUUAGAAUAAAACAACAUUAUUAGUCAUUGAAGAAAAUCUGAUUUCUUUUUCUUUUUUCUUCACCAGCAGAAUAGAAUUAAAUGGUACUGCCAUAUUAUUAUUUACACUGUGUUUAUAACAGGAUUCCCUCCUUUUCAGAGUCUUUAUGGAAACUUUGAAAGUAGAUGUUUGACUAAGGUCCGGAGCACAUGCCCUUCUGGACAUGACUUUGUGCUAUUUUUGGAAUUUGGAAAGCAAUGGAAUAAUGACUCUAGCUUUCAGUUUCUCUGUUACAUGGCCAGUGUCUUCCAAAUGCUCUUUGUGAAAUUGAAUGUGAGAUAAUUUUUGAGAGGAGCAGAUGGGUGUGUGAAUAGCCAUUUUAAACCCAUCUCAACCUUUAAAGAUGGUCUUGGUGCUUUAGUGUACUUCUGCUGAAAAAAAAAAAAAUUAAAGCUGGUUCAGACGAAUACUUUUGUAUCCUUUCUGAAAACAAAUGGCCUUUUUCUUUUUCCUUUUUGAUGCUCUUUUACCCUACUCUUCAACUACAACGUAAUUAUUUUCAGUUUCACAUACCAUGUUCUUAUUCAGGCUAUUUUAAAAAUAAAAGAAGCUCCGGGGAUGUUGUACAUUUAAUAUAUGUCCAGGCAAACCAGAUGGUGGUGGUUCAUAUUUUUAAUCUUUCGAUAAGUGAUCGUGAAAAAAAAAAAAAAAAGAGCUACUGGCCUUUUCCUUCCCGCCUAGGACAAGCAACCCAAUGGCUUCACUGUGUGGCUGUCUUGUUUUUCAGGUGAAAUAUCAUAAGUCAAGAUAUGGUUAUGCAUAUCCAAAAGAUCAGACUAAGGCCCUGAUAGUGUGUAUGACCAAAACUUUCCUCUUCUACUAGCAAGACAAAAAUCCACAACUUUUUAGAGAAAUGGCUAGAUUUUAAAGGCAAUCUGUAAUGGCUGAAUCUUUUAUUUUGCCUCUUGAAUCAUACAGCAGUUUGUGAGAGUCAAAUAUUUGAUAGCUGAUUGAAAAUAAAUGAAAUGUGAGCGCAUUUCAGUGGAAGUAGGCCAGUUGCUAACAUUCUCUUCUAUCUCUGAAAGUUAAAUUUCAUUAUUUAAUUGGAUAAAAAUCAAGAGCAAUAUUUGUCAUAUGGGGGAAUUUCUAUAUAAGGUCACUCUAUUGGGCGGCGGGGAAUGGUCUCGUGGCCUUUUUUGGGUGUUAACUCUAUUGUUUCUUAUGUUGAAAUAACCCAUUCCUGUGAGUGGUAUUUGUAGUUAACCUUCUUGAAAACUUCAUAUUCAGGUACCAUGUCUUUGAGGACAUGGUUCUUGGAUCAGCGUGCGGCUUCCACAGCAUUGCGCCGGGCUUCUGCUACAGCCAGGCAUGUUUUCUGCGGCUGAAUUAGGCCUGGAGAAUGUUGCAUCUUAAAACCUGCUUUUCAGCGUGCAUUUGUAGAGCAUAAGCCAUCAUCCCUCUGUAGACCCACUCGUUUCUACAAGGGAUGGAAAAAUUUAACCUUUAAGUGCCAUAAAAUAUUGGAGGAGUAGGGAGAAAAUAGUACAAGAAAACAAGUUUGAACUUGUACUAUGUGGUUUUAUAUGGAAGCUUUCUAUUAUUAUGCCUAUAUUCCCAAUUAUAUUUUUCUAACUACUUCAGGACAAGUAUGAAUUUAGUUAUUUAGUAUAGUCAUCUAGUUUCUUAAUAUGGUAAAUUUAAUUUCAGGUUUCUUUGCUUUUUUAUAUCAUUGUAGUAUCACAGCUAUGGCAAUAUAAAGAAAGUAAGUUAUUCUUUAUAUUUAUUGGUCACUUGCUUUUAAAUCAGUUAUAUGCUUUUAAAUAAAUUUGAAGGUCAUUUUGGUUAUGGCUAUAAUAAGAUGUAUCACAAACCACCCUUGACUAGAAUGUGAAUGCCAAAGUGUUGAACUUAUUUAGAAAAUGUUUAGAUUAUUUAGAUUAUAUCAGUGUAUAGAAUUAUGCAUAUAGUAUAGAUAUGUAUCAUAUAAAUGUAUACAAUUUAAAAUGCUUAUAUAGUUUUUCAGGGUGUACAUUAGUGAUUUAAAAAAUACAGCAGUAAAGUUCUUUAUGUAUCCAGUGACUAAAGCAUAUCAGGUAGUAGAUCAUAAUUCGUAAGCUGAUGUAAUUUAAUAAGAAGGUGAUUCACAAUUUAAUUUAUAAAUGUAGGUAAAUGCAUAACUUUAGAAAUUUGAUACAAUAUUUUCAUAACUUCAUACAAUUAAAACAUAGGUACUUUCCUAUGAUAAAUAUGUGACCUAGGGCAUUAAAAAAUAAUGUAGUAGCAUUUCUGACUAAGAAGAUUAAAUUGGCCAGAUGCAGUGGCUCAUGCCUAUAAUCCCAACACUUUGGGAGGCCAAGGUGGAUGAAUCACUUGAGCCCAGGAGUUUGAGACCAGCCUGGGCAAUAUGGCAAAACCCUAUCUCUACAAAAAAUUUAAAAAUCAUCCAGGUGGGCCAGGCACGGUGGCUCACGCCUGUAAUCCCAGCACUUUGGGAGGCCGAGGCAGGCUGAUCACGAAGUCAGGAGAUCAAGACCAUCCUGGCUAACAUGGUGAAACCCCGUCUCUACUAAAAAUACAAAAAAUUAGCCAAUCAUGGUGGCGGGCGCCUGUAGUCCCAGCUACUAGAGAGGCUGAGGCAGGAGAAUUGUGUGAACCCAGGAAGCGGAGCUUGCAGUGAGCCGAGACUGCGCCACUGCACUCCAGCCUGGGUGACAGAGCGAGACUCCGUCUCAAAAAAAUAAAUAAAUAAAUAUAAAAGUUAGCCAGGCACGGUGGCAUGCACCUACAGCCCCAGCUACUUGGGAGGCUGAGAUGGGAGAAUCAGUUGCGUCUGGGAUGUUGAGGAUACAGUGAGCCAUGAUCAUGCCACAGCACUCCAGUCUGGGCCACAGAAUGAGACCCUGUCCCAAGGGGGAAAAAAAAAAGAUUAAAUCAUGACUGAGGCAGAUUCUUCAACUUGGGAAAACUGACUUUAUGUCAACCUUCAUAGAUAAGGAAGCCUCCCAUAAAACACUUUUUAGUGAAAUGCAAACUAAUCUACCGUCUUCUAAGCUUUGGUUCAUAAGAGUCCUGGGAGCUUGCAAAAGCUUUGCCAAGAUUCCCUCUGAGCAUUCCUUGAGGGGCUUUCUAGAGCCUGGAAGAUUAUCUUUAUAAUCAGAAAAUCUCUGUAAUAACUGUAAAGCAAUUCUCCAUGAAAUGGGUUCUACUCCUUGGACAAUAGCAGAAUGGUGGCAGGGUUUUUUCCUUGUCCAUUGUCAAAAGAUAUGUUGUGCCUCAUAAUGCCAGGAGGAGAGAGGUGAACUGUGAUCACUGUCCCUCUCUAUCUUAAGAUGUAUAAAUACAUAACCUCCAGAGCUAUUAGAGAUUAUUUAUGUCCAAACAAGUUAAUCACAUUCACAAAUAUAUGUAAUCUAAUGACCUUCCCAAUAACAAAAAAAUACAACCAGAGGUCCAUAUGUGUAAACGAUUGAUUCCGUUGUCAUUCAGGUUAGUGGUUAUUAGGACUUGUGCUGUAAAGGAUUUGCUUUAAAUAUGUAUGUAUUUGUAUUAAACAUAAGACACCUGCAGAAUACAUGGAAGAAUUAUAAUGUGAAAAAUUAAACAUCUCACAAUUAUAUUAGCAGUGGUAACAUGGGAAGUGAAGGGUGAGUAUAUUUUCUAAAGUUUUCAAAUGGAAAAGUACCUGUGUGUGUAUACAUGUAUAAUUACUUUUUUAUUAUUAACAUAUUAUUUUUUAUUAAAUCAUUCCUAUUUAAUAAGACAAUGCAUUUUCUAAUAUAAUUACAUAGACUCUUUCAGGACCAGACUUGACUUAUAUAUCAAAAUGGAGAGAUAGAAUUAUCUAAAGACUAUAAUUCUCUCUAUAAAGUGACAUUAAAAGGUAUUCAAACAUUCAUCGAUUCACUCUUCAUGAACUCAACUUAACUAUUCAGUGUCUAUUCUAUACUUGGUGAUACACUGGAUCUUUUGGUAUAUAUAUGUGUCUAUAUGUAUGUAGUUGGUAUACGUGUGUGUAUAUAUAGAUGUAUGUAAAUAUGUACAUAUAUUUAUGAGAAUAUUUAGUCAAAGGAAACAAGUAUAAUAGAUUAAAUGCUCUAUAAAAUUUAGCAUGAAGAAAAUCAUGCAAGAAAGAAUGGCUUCAUACAGGAAGUUGAGGUUUACUAUGAUAAGGCUCAGAAGUUAUUAAGUUUGGAUUAGCCAAGAGGACAAAAAAGCAUGAAACUUUCUAUAACUAACCUCAAAUACUUUGGUUUCUUAUUGUUAUUACUUAUAAAGUGGAUAUUAAUAGCUGUCACUCAUCAAAAGCCAUAGUAAUUAACCCAUAAACUACCAGUGAAAUUGGAAGAAAAAGUGGCUGAGACCAAACAAUUAUCCAGUAUUUUCUUAGUUACACCAGAAGCUGCUACAAUUCUACCCAGCAGUAAUUUUCCUAGGUCUUUCUUAAAUGAAUAAAAAUAUCCUGGCUAUAAGAAGCAGAAAAAUCCUAGGAGAGGAGAAGAUGUCUUGGCUUUCCCACCUCUCCAUAAUGUAGAGGAAAUUAAUGGUAAAAAAAAAAAAAAAAAAAAAAAUUGUGCUAUCAUGACCCUAAGAACUAUCAGCCAAAAGUGAUGGCCUAGCUUCUCUAUUUACCAUACUCCAACCUAGGAGGUACUCUACUAAAAAACUGUAUUUUGACUUAAAGUAAUUUUCAUAAUAUAUAUAUUUGGACAUGGCUAAUGUCAGGUUAAUAUCAACUUUAAAGUAACACCACAGAAAGUAUCAUCUGGAUACUACCCUUUAAUUAGUUCACAUUGUAAAAUAUUAAACUACAUUUGCAUUACGUCUUCAUUAAAUCAGGAAUUUUGAGCCAAAUUUCCCCAACAUGAACUGUGUUUAUGGCCUUUUUAAAAAUAACACAGUAACUCUUUCAGAAGGCUUUGGCAGAGUGACCCUAACACUCAGCUACCAAAGUUAAUGGGGGCUUUGAAAUCAUUAACAUGUCCAUGCACUAUUGUUUCAUCUUAAAAGCUUUACAUUAUCUAGGUUGUGCUGUGCGUCAUGUCUUUGCAACUGUUUUCAUAAAACUUUGCACAAUCCUGUCUUCCCAAGUGAUCUCAGAGUACUUAUUAUUUAUUCUUGUAAUAUUACAGUGGCUCUUCUAGCCAUGUGGCAUGUCACAAUGAUUUAGUUAAAGGAAGUAUUCACAGCCGGAUCACACAUUGAAUUCAGAAUGUGCUCCUAAUGAAAGUCUAUAGAGAUUCUGGACAAUGCCAUUUAUGAGGAAAUUUCCAUUUCAUUUAGAAUUCUUUGACAAGUAUUGAAUUCAGUUAUGCAGUUCAAAAAAAGAGAGAGAUCCAUCAUUUUUCUUCUAGUAAAAUAAGAAGAAAAUUAUGUAAGCCAGAGAAAAAUAGAGCUCAAAGUUGAAAUAUGACUGUGACUAAUGUUAAUGUGCUGCUCUUUCUUUCUAAAAUUAUAGAAACAUGGACAAUACUUAGAAACAACUGGUAAUAUUCUUUGCCCUUUGAAAAUUUCCAUCUGAAGAGGUGGAAAUUAAAAAUUUGAUUUGAUGUAUUUUAAUUAACAUAAUCAUGGCUAGAUGUCAGCAUACCACUUUAUCCAACUAUUCUUGGUUUGGCCUCAAUGUAUUAAGUUAUAUUCAUAUGGCAUUCAUAUACAAAUGCAGAUCAUUAAACAAGUUAAUCAGUAUAAUCCAUCCAUUCCAGACCACCCACAUUGAAUGUUGUCUAAACUUUUUUUGUCUGAUUCAGGUCAGUAGUCACGUUAUUUUGAAUAGUACAACUUGAUUUAUGUUAAAUUAUUAGUACAUAAUGAUCAGUAAUGCUAAUAGAGUUAAAUGCUAUCACUACUAUUUUUUUUUCACACAAUGACACAGUAUUUCCCAGUUAGUUAAAUAAAAGGGGGAAAAUCACAUCUUUGAAAUGGGAUUUUG